AGACGCUCUCUUUGCUUUUCCCCACGAGUGACCACGGCUAGAUAGGCCGCCGGCCAGAUGUGGCGGGGGAGAGCCGGGGCUUUGCUCCGGGUGUGGGGGUUUUGGCCGACAGGGGUUCCCAGAAGGAGACCGCUAAGCUGCGAUGCUGCGUCGCAGGCGGGAAGCAAUUAUCCCCGCUGUUGGAACUGCGGCGGCCCAUGGGGCCCCGGGCGGGAGGACAGGUUCUUCUGCCCACAGUGCCGAGCGCUGCAGGCACCUGACCCCACUCGAGACUACUUCAGCCUUAUGGACUGGUACGAGCGACGGUUUCGGGAAACGGGCCCGGGCGAGAGACACGUCGAGCAACCGUUCCUUCAGAGUUGAUACAGCGAAGCUCCAGCACAGGUACCAGCAACUGCAGCGUCUUGUCCACCCAGAUUUCUUCAGCCAGAGGUCUCAGACUGAAAAGGACUUCUCAGAGAAGCAUUCGACCCUGGUGAAUGAUGCCUAUAAGACCCUCCUGGCCCCCCUGAGCAGAGGACUGUACCUUCUAAAGCUCCAUGGAAUAGAGAUUCCUGAAAGGACAGAUUAUGAAAUGGACAGGCAAUUCCUCAUAGAAAUAAUGGAAAUCAAUGAAAAACUCGCAGAAGCUGAAAGUGAAGCUGCCAUGAAAGAGAUUGAAUCCAUUGUCAAAGCUAAACAGAAAGAAUUUACUGACAAUGUGAGCAGUGCUUUUGAACAAGAUGACUUUGAAGAAGCCAAGGAAAUUUUGACAAAGAUGAGAUACUUUUCAAAUAUAGAAGAAAAGAUCAAGUUAAAGAAGAUUCCCCUUUAAUUGUGGAUAGUUUAAAGUUUAAAAAAUAAAGUUCUUGCUGGGCACAGUGGCUCACACCUGUAAUCCCAGCACUUUGGGAGGCUGAGGUGGGUGGAUGACAAGGUCAGGAGUUCAAGACCAGCUUGGCCAACAUAGUGAAACCCCGUCUCUGCUGAAAAUACAAAAAUUAGCCGGGCAUGGUGGCGCGUGCCUGUAAUCCCAGCUACUUGGUAGGCCGAGGCAGGAGAAUCGCUUAAACCCGUGAGGUGGAGGUUGCAGUGAGCAGAGAUCACGCAACUGCACUCCAGCUUGGGCAACAGAGUGAGACUUAAUCUUGAAAAAUAAAUAAAUGAAAAAUAAAA